UGAAGUGGUGUGAGGACCCCACCUGCUCCCCAUCACCAGGGCGUGGGGCCCUUAUCAAGCCGAGACGUCACUGUUUAGUAUCAAAUGCCAAAGUCUAAGUCGGGACCAUCCACAGUGUCCCCGAUGACACCAGAUAGGGGAGGUCCCCAGGUUCCCCAGCUCAUGGCCUGCACCCUCGGCACUAGCCUUCCAGUCAGGACCAGCAAGGGAGCCGGGGAGCUGGAGCCCCUUCGAGUCUACCCCUGAAACUGGACUGGGCUCGCCUGACAACUGCCUGAGGUCAUUGUAGCCAUCCCCCUGUGGAUGGAGAAAGGGGGAUGGUCACUGAGGCCUGCAGGGCGUAGAGAGGGAGGGUGGCGGCCAAGGGCUCAAUUCAGGGGACCCAGGGGUGUGAAUCCAGCUUGUGAGGACAGGGCCGGGGCAGGAGGAAAUGUCUCUGACACGCGCGUCCCCCCCAGCAGAUCUAGACCUGGGCCUGGGUCUGUCCCUGCCCGAAAUCCAUGCCGAGUUCCCUUCCCGGCAGCCAGGUCCCCCACCCCACUCUGGACGCGGUUGACCUAGUGGAAAAGACUCUGAGGAAUGAAGGCCUCUUACGCCUCAGCCCGUCCUCCGGCCUGUGCCCUUGUGCCCCCAGUUGGAGGGAGGUGGUCCUGGAAACAGCCGUACUCAAUUCUACCUCCACAGGGACCUCCAGUUCUGCUCCAGUCUUGGAGGAAGGGGACACAGACCCCUGGACCCUCCCUCAGCUGAAGGACACAAGCCAGCCCUGGAAAGAGCUCCGCGUGGCCGGCAGGCUGCGCCGCGUGGCCGGCAGCGUCCUCAAGGCCUGCGGGCUCCUCGGCAGCCUGUACUUCUUCAUCUGCUCUCUGGACGUCCUCAGCUCCGCCUUCCAGCUGCUGGGCAGCAAAGUGGCCGGAGACAUCUUCAAGGACAACGUGGUGCUGUCCAACCCUGUGGCUGGACUGGUCAUUGGCGUGCUGGUCACAGCCCUGGUGCAGAGUUCCAGCACGUCCUCCUCCAUCGUGGUCAGCAUGGUGGCUGCUAAGCUGCUGACUGUCCGGGUGUCUGUGCCCAUCAUCAUGGGUGUCAACGUAGGCACAUCCAUCACCAGCACCCUGGUCUCAAUGGCGCAGUCAGGGGACCGGGAUGAAUUUCAGAGGGCUUUCAGCGGCUCGGCGGUGCACGGGAUCUUCAACUGGCUCACAGUGCUGGUCCUGCUGCCACUGGAGAGCGCCACGGCCCUGCUGGAGAGGCUAAGUGAGCUAGCCCUGGGUGCCGCCAGCCUGACACCCAGGGCGCAGGCGCCCGACAUCCUCAAGGUGCUGACGAAGCCGCUCACACACCUCAUCGUGCAGUUGGACUCCGACAUGAUCAUGAGCAGUGCCACAGGCAACGCCACUAACAGCAGUCUCAUUAAGCACUGGUGCGGCACCACGGGGCAGCCGACCCAGGAGAACAGCAGCUGUGGCGCCUUCGGCCCGUGCACAGAGAAGAACAGCACAGCCCCGGCGGACAGGCUGCCCUGCCGCCACCUGUUUGCGGGCACGGAGCUCACGGACCUGGCCGUGGGCUGCAUCCUGCUGGCCGGCUCCCUGCUGGUGCUCUGCGGCUGCCUGGUCCUCAUAGUCAAGCUGCUCAACUCUGUGCUGCGCGGCCGCGUGGCCCAGGUCGUGAGGACAGUCAUCAAUGCGGACUUCCCCUUCCCGCUGGGCUGGCUCGGCGGCUACCUGGCCGUCCUCGCGGGCGCCGGCCUGACCUUCGCACUGCAGAGCAGCAGCGUCUUCACGGCGGCCGUCGUGCCCCUCAUGGGGGUCGGGGUGAUCAGUCUGGACCGGGCGUACCCCCUCUUACUGGGCUCCAACAUCGGCACCACUACCACAGCCCUGCUGGCUGCCCUGGCCAGCCCCGCAGACAGGAUGCUCAGCGCCCUGCAGCCCGUCUGCGGCCUGCUGCCCGGAGGCCCAACAGGUUCAGCUCCCGAAACUCCGGGUCAUGCUGCACCGCCGCUGACAGGAAGAGACAAGUGCGGCACCCCCUGGAACCCACGCUCGUUCUUCUUGCCUCUGCCCUGUCUCUAUCCACUUAGACCCUCCCAGUGCAGGGUCCUGCUCCACCCCCUGCAGGAAGCCCUCCAGACUGCACCUGUGUGUGGACUCCUCCAAGUCCGGCAGCCCCUGGAGGGGCCCGUGACACUGUUCUCCCCUCCUGUGGCCCUGUGCCUCCUCCCCGCAGGGCCUGGACUGUGCAGGCUCAGCACACUGGGGACUGAGGAGACGGGGUCUCUUGGCAGGAGGCACAGGCAGAGCCAGGUCGGAAGGUCGCCCUCAUCCACUUCUUCUUCAACCUGGCCGGCAUCCUGCUGUGGUACCUGGUGCCUGCACUGCGGCUGCCCAUCCCGCUGGCCAGGCACUUCGGGGUGGUGACCGCCCGUUACCGCUGGGUGGCUGGGGUCUACCUGCUGCUCGGAUUCCUGCUGCUGCCCCUGGCGGCCUUCGGGCUCUCCCUGGCAGGGGGCAUGGAGCUGGCCGCUGUCGGGGGUCCCCUGGUGGGGCUGGUGCUCCUCGUCAUCCUGGUUACUGUCCUGCAGCGGCGCCGGCCGGCCUGGCUGCCUGUCCGCCUGCGCUCCUGGGCCUGGCUCCCCGUCUGGCUCCAUUCUCUGGAGCCCUGGGACCGCCUGGUGACCCGCUGCUGCCCCUGCAACGUCUGCAGCCCCCCGAAGGCCACCACCAAAGAGGCCUACUGCUACGAGAACCCUGAGAUCUUGGCCUCCCAGCAGUUGUGACGGGCAGUUGCUGAGCAGACCGCCCCACCCUCCCCGGCUGGGAGGGCUCUGGAGGGCCCUGGAGGGGGGGUCCCCGCGGCAGCUGACCUCCGGUCACCUGCUUCCCCUUCUGUGCAAAUAAACCAGGCUGUUAUCUGGG